AUUCCAUUCACAGACUCUUGUUGGGCAGCAGCCACCCGCUCACCUCCAUCCCCAGGACUUAGAGGGACGCAGGGCGUUGGGAACAGAGGACACUCCAGGCGCUGACCCUGGGAGGCCAGGACCAGGGCCAAAGUCCCGUGGGCAAGAGGAGUCCUCAGAGGUCCUUCAUUCAGCGGUUCCGGGAGGUCUGGGAAGCCCACGGCCUGGCUGGGGCAGGGUCAACGCCGCCAGGCCGCCAUGGUCCUGUGCUGGCUGCUGCUUCUGGUGAUGGCUCUGCCCCCAGGCACGACGGGCGUCAAGGACUGCGUCUUCUGUGAGCUCACCGACUCCAUGCAGUGUCCUGGUACCUACAUGCACUGUGGCGAUGACGAGGACUGCUUCACAGGCCACGGGGUCGCCCCGGGCACUGGUCCGGUCAUCAACAAAGGCUGCCUGCGAGCCACCAGCUGCGGCCUUGAGGAACCCGUCAGCUACAGGGGCGUCACCUACAGCCUCACCACCAACUGCUGCACCGGCCGCCUGUGUAACAGAGCCCCGAGCAGCCAGACAGUGGGGGCCACCACCAGCCUGGCACUGGGGCUGGGUAUGCUGCUUCCUCCACGUUUGCUGUGACCAACAGGGAGGACAGGGCCUGGGACUGUUCUCCCAGAUCCGCCACUCCCCAUGUCCCCAUGUCCUUCCCCCACUAAAUGGCCAGAGAGGCCCUGGACAACCUCUUGCGGCCCUGGCUUCAUCCCUUCUAAGGCUGUCCACCAGGAGCCCGGUGCUAGGGGAAGCAUCCCCAGGCCUGACUGAGCGGCAGGGGAGCACGGCCCGUGGGUUUGAUUGUAUUACUCUGUUCCACUGGUUCUAAGACGCAGAGCUUCUCACAUCUCAAUCAGGAUGCUUCUCUCCAUUGGUAGCACUUUAGAGUCCAUGAAAUAUGGUAAAAAAUAUAUAUAUAUCAUAAUAAAUGACAGCUGAUGUUCAUGGA